ACUCUGCUGCCGGCUUCUCGGAGCGGCGCUGGGCGACCAGAGCAGGGUCGAGAUGUCCUACAUCCCGGGCCAGCCGGUCACCGCCGUGGUGCAAAGAGUUGAAAUUCACAAGCUGCGUCAAGGUGAGAACUUAAUCCUGGGUUUCAGCAUUGGAGGUGGAAUCGACCAGGAUCCUUCCCAGAAUCCCUUCUCUGAAGACAAGACGGACAAGGGUAUUUAUGUCACACGGGUGUCUGAAGGAGGCCCUGCUGAAAUCGCUGGGCUGCAGAUUGGAGACAAGAUCAUGCAGGUGAACGGCUGGGACAUGACCAUGGUCACACACGACCAGGCCCGCAAGCGGCUCACCAAGCGCUCGGAGGAGGUGGUGCGUCUGCUGGUGACGCGGCAGUCGCUGCAGAAGGCCGUGCAGCAGUCCAUGCUGUCCUAGCAGCCACCACCAUCUGCGACUCCUGCCUGCCGCCUCUCUGUACAGUAACGCCACUUCCACACUCUGUCCCCAUCUGGCUUCUGCUGACCGCUGGGCCCCAGCUCAGAAGGGCUAUAGCUGGUCCCAGAGGCCUGGCCUGGCCUUCCUUCCCUUCUCCCAUCCCUGGCCUGGGGCCUCUGGGACCGGCUUUCUCUCCUGGACACCGAGGAUUGGAAAUAAGGGCCUGGAGCUGAGUAGUAGCCAGUCUGCUGUGACCACAGGCUCAGGUCCGACCCUGCUGCUUGGCCACAGCAGUGGCUGGGCAAGUGGGAACCACUAUCUCUUGGGAGCCCCCAAAAGCUGGGAAAUGCUGGAGGAACCAGGCCUUUCCCGCUUUUGCCUGGCUGCAGGGUUCGGCUCCGCCCCUGCCCCCCAGCCCUCGUGUGUCCACACCGCAGUGCCUCUGCCCCUCGGGGGACUGGACACACAUCCUGCCAGAGGCGCUACGAAGCUUUGCCCAGAUGAAGCCAGGUGGGCUCCGCGUUCACUCCCACUCUCCCGAGGGGUGCUGGCCUCCCCAGGGUUUGCCUUCUUACGGAUUUAGACGAGGUUCGAGGCUCACCUAUCAGGGCAGCUCUCAGGAUUGUCAUUUUCCUCUUUGCCUGUGGGUUUAACUUUUGUAUUUUUUUAAUCACAAGUUUGAUACAAAAUGUUUUUAUCGUACUCUUUGGAGAUGCCCAUUCUACUUUUGAAUUUAGCUUUUACUAAUUCGCAUCUGGAAGCUCAGCAAGUGCACAAGCCUUACUUUGGUUACCGUGGAAACCACUGCCGCCCCUCCCCGAUGUGGUGCGCUCAAUAAAAAUGCUGGAAUUCA